ACAACAAUCCCGCAGUUCAAAGUUAAGCAGCAGUUGCACAACUUCCAGCAACUUUCUCAGCCGGCUACUAAUGAGCUGAAAGCCAGGAACAUCCGAGGAGAAGAGAAAGCUUCCAGCCCUCCUCCCUUCACCCUGGAAAUCCAGACACCCCCACCCCCACCCUCAGAUCACUUUAAGAUAAUUUCUUUAUUCGUUUGCCCGACAGACCAUGGCUCCCUUUGGAAGAAACUUGCUAAAGACUCGGCAUAAAAACAGAUCUCCAACUAAAGACAUGGAUUCAGAAGAGAAGGAAAUUGUGGUUUGGGUUUGCCAAGAAGAGAAGCUUGUCUGUGGGCUGACUAAACGCACCACCUCUGCUGAUGUCAUCCAGGCUUUGCUUGAGGAACAUGAGGCUACGUUUGGAGAGAAACGAUUUCUUCUGGGGAAGCCCAGUGAUUACUGCAUCAUAGAGAAGUGGAGAGGCUCCGAAAGGGUUCUUCCUCCACUAACUAGAAUCCUGAAGCUUUGGAAAGCGUGGGGAGAUGAGCAGCCCAAUAUGCAAUUUGUUUUGGUUAAAGCAGAUGCUUUUCUUCCAGUUCCUUUGUGGCGGACAGCUGAAGCCAAAUUAGUGCAAAACACAGAAAAAUUGUGGGAGCUCAGCCCAGCAAACUACAUGAAGACUUUACCACCAGAUAAACAAAAAAGAAUAGUCAGGAAAACUUUCCGGAAACUGGCUAAAAUUAAGCAGGACACAGUUUCUCAUGAUCGAGAUAAUAUGGAGACAUUAGUUCAUCUGAUCAUUUCCCAGGACCAUACUAUUCAUCAGCAAGUCAAGAGAAUGAAAGAGCUGGAUCUGGAAAUUGAAAAGUGUGAAGCUAAGUUCCAUCUUGAUCGAGUAGAAAAUGAUGGAGAAAACUAUGUUCAGGAUGCAUAUUUAAUGCCCAGUUUCAGUGAAGUUGAGCAAAAUCUAGACUUGCAGUAUGAGGAAAACCAGACUCUGGAGGACCUGAGCGAAAGUGAUGGAAUUGAACAGCUGGAAGAACGACUGAAAUAUUACCGAAUACUCAUUGAUAAGCUCUCUGCUGAAAUAGAAAAAGAGGUAAAAAGUGUUUGCAUUGAUAUAAAUGAAGAUGCGGAAGGGGAAGCUGCAAGUGAACUGGAAAGCUCUAAUUUAGAGAGUGUUAAGUGUGAUUUGGAGAAAAGCAUGAAAGCUGGUUUGAAAAUUCACUCUCAUUUGAGUGGCAUCCAGAAAGAGAUUAAAUACAGUGACUCAUUGCUUCAGAUGAAAGCAAAAGAAUAUGAACUCCUGGCCAAGGAAUUCAAUUCACUUCACAUUAGCAACAAAGAUGGGUGCCAGUUAAAGGAAAACAGAGCGAAGGAAUCUGAGGUUCCCAGUAGCAAUGGGGAGAUUCCUCCCUUUACUCAAAGAGUAUUUAGCAAUUACACAAAUGACACAGACUCGGACACUGGUAUCAGUUCUAACCACAGUCAGGACUCCGAAACAACAGUAGGAGAUGUGGUGCUGUUGUCAACAUAGUUCCAAUGGCUCCUUUCUGACCUGCUUUCAUGUUUUAAUGUUUGUUUAAUUUAAUAGGAAACCUCAUUUUAAAUAUAACACUCAAAAAAAUGUAAAUCAUAUUGUAGUAUUCAAUAGUUAAUAAAAACUCGAGAAAUGUGUUGUUUCUGAUGUGAAAUUUCCAAAGGAACUUUAAUUAUUGCAAGUUCAAGCAAUGAACUAUUUAUCACGAAUGCAGCACAAAUAGCUUGUCGUUGUAGAACACAGAAAUAAUUUGAUGGGAAUCAUAUGAUAAUCUUCCUUAGCGUCUGUGGAAAACGAUUUACAUAAACUUUAAAAGCAAUCCUCAAUAUUAGACAGUCCAAAUAUUCAAACAUGAAGAAGUAGAAUUAAAAUGUGCUGUAAUAUAUAUUUUUCCAACACUGUAUAAUUGGAAUUUUUAAAUCUGUAAAGUAUAUGGGAGCUACUGUGUUGUAACUGCAUUAAUUCAAAGUUUGGUUCUUUUAAUUGAUCCUUGAUAAUACAACGUAUCAUGUAUAUCACUUCCUGAACCCUUCUACCUGUUGAGGCCUAUGAAACAGGCUGCUGUUGGGACAUGUAUAAAUACUGGCAGGGAAUCAGACACGUAUAGGGUACAGAUGAGGCAGGGCCAAGUGCUGCAUACAAACAGCAAUUUUUAUAAAGAAGCCUCAAUUUAUUAAGAGCUAUGUGUGGAUGUUUGCUAUCUGGCAAUUCAGAUCUCCUGACCAAACCCAUGUUCAUUCACUGAGUGAGGUAUAGUGUGGGUUACAGAGAAAAUCAGUCAUAGUGUUAUUUGUUUAUGUCCUAUCUACAAAAGUUGCAAUGAUGGAAUUUGGAACCCUUCUGUGGAUAAAAUAGAAUCUGCUAUAAUUAUUAGCAUUUUGUCUCUGAACCUACAGAGAGGAGACCACAUGGACAAAAGACUUAUUCUGCUAUGCUAUAACUCAGAUUGUCUUAUUUCUUCAUCUAAAGUGCUUAAAAGAGACUUAGUUCCUAAAAAAGUACCAGCAAAAUCCCCAACACACUAGUAAGAAUUCAAGAAAUUGAAGGGAUUAUUUAGGUCUUAUCUUGACUGACAAUCAUUAUUAUGGCCUACUAUGCUUGUGUUUUAAUUAGAAAUGUGCUUUCUUCUCUCUCCCUUCUUUGCUUACUUUCUUCUUAUUUGCCUUCCUGUCUGCCUUACUUCCUCUCUUUUCCUGCCUUCAUCUCUCCUUCUCCCGUCUUCUUUUUUUCCUUUGCUUCCUUCCUGCCAAUGAACACAUGAUGCAAUCAUAAUGAAAUAAUUAUUUUUUAUUGUACUGUUAACUGAGUACUGCUGCAGUUUAUUUUUAUUUAGCUGAUAUCUUUCCUGUGUGUCACUGCACAUGUAAGUAGAAAUAUUAUUUUACUUAGUUUUAAUAUGUGGACAUUGGUUAAGGGUCCCAAUCCUUCUCAUUUCUUCUCUUUUAUUCUUUUGCAUACUUUUAGUGCAGGUUUUAACUCAGUUUUCUUAUUGUUUUACUUUCAAAAUUUGAAAAGUAUUUAAUUUUUUAAAGCAACUUUAUUGUUAACUCAUUUAAAAAAAUAUAUUGCUCCUUAAAUCUUCUUAACAUAUUUGUUCCUGCCUUCUCCUGUCUUUUAACUCAUCUUUGGGAAGACAUUUAGAAUUUUCUGAUUGUUUCAGUUUCGUGAGCAUUUAUACUAUCAUUUCUUGUACCAAAAUAGAUAUUUUCAGGUCUUAUUUCAAGUUGGCUGGUAAGAAAAAUAGAAAUUUCCAUUCUAUGGAAAAAUACAGUGAUAAAGAGUAAUAAUUCUGGCAUCGGUUACAUUUUUUUAAAAAAGAUAAAAUUGAAUAGUCAUCUGUGAAAGGAAAGUUCACCUGACUAAGAGUCCAUAAAAUUAUUCAACAAUAUAAGCCACUGACAUAUUCAUUGUUCACUAAUGGGGAUCAAAUUCAGAAGAUCAUCGUAAAUGAUAAACCCAUUGUAUCAUUUUCCUACAGUGGAAGUCAUCUCUUUGAAUUAUUCUUAUCUUUAGUGAGAAAAUACUGAAAGAACAUGCUUAUCUAUUUGACUAAUUAUCUGAAUUCAAGAGGUUCUGAUAAGAAGUAGGCCUGGAGAGAUAAUUUCAUCUUAGAAACUUUGAAUUAACUUCUGCUUUUAUACAGUUAAGCACAGUAAUGCAUUUAAGGCUCAAUUCUUCUACAUUUUACAGUAAAUAAUGUUUGUAAGUCUCAGAAAGCAGUACCAUUGCUUUUUAAAUUCAUUUCAGAAUUUCCAUUUGCUCAUUAGUUAUACAAAUGUAUUUGUGCGUUUGAUCACUACAAUCAUUAAGUUUUAAUCCUUCAUCAGCUACCAUGGUGAACCUCUUAAUUUACAGUUACAUGUUAAUAUAUUAACACAAAUAGAAGUACUGAAAUACAAUGCCCUCAUGUCUGGAUACUGAACUAUUUGUUAUUAAAUUAAGUGAGAAUUGGAAUUAUAAGUAUAGAACUUGAUAGAAAGUGUAAUGUUAUUAUCUAUAGAAAUGUUAAAGUAUAAAUUCUUGAGUAAUCUGACAGGUUAACUAUGAAAUUGCUAUAUGCAGCUAGAAGAAACAAACCAAAGCUGACUAUUCUUAAUUUCUGUAACAGGACCUAGAUUCAUCCUUGGUCAUCCUUCCACUUGGAAUUCUCCUUUUUAUCCUUCUGCAAUGCUCUGAAAUCUUACCCUUUCCACAGUCUUUUUAAUGUGCUAGCUCUUCUAUGAUAUACGUUUGUUCCAUUCAAUUAGUUGGAAUCUCAUCUCUGAACCCAGAAAUAUUUUAGAGGUACUUCUCAUAAGAAGCAUUUUUAUUCUGGCUUACGCUAUAUAUAUUUAUGCACUUACCUAAUUCCCCUCCUUCAAUGAAUUCUAUUUUUUUUUUCCUUGAGACGGAGUCUCACUCUGUCGCCCAGGCUGGAGUGCAGUGGCGCGAUCUUGGCUCACUGCAAGCUCCGCCUCCCGGCUUCACGCCAUUUUCCUGCCUCAGCCUCCUGAGUAGCUGGGACUACAGGCGCCCGCCACCACGCCAGGCUAAUUUUUUUGUAUUUUUUUAGUAGAGACGGGGUUUCACCGUGUUAGCCAGGAUGGUCUCGAUGUCCUGACCUUGUGAUCCACCCGUCUUGGCCUCCCAAAGUGCUGGGAUUACAGGCGUGAGCCACCGUGCCCGACCAAUGAAUUCUUAUUAAAUUACUUUAUCAUCUGUCUUGUUAGCCUUACUCUUUCCUAUUAACUUCUUUGCCCCCUGCUCCCUUUUUGAAUUGAGUGGCUAAAUUUUAGAGGUUUGUAGCUUUUGUGUGUGUGUGUGUGUGUUUUAUAGAUGGUAAAUGAUGCUUGUACAUUUUGUACAUGAAUGAAUACGUAUUUUAGCAGACUUAAAACAUUAACAGUAAUUGACCUUAUACAUUUUGGGAAAGAAAAAUUAAAUCUUCAUGCUACUACGAUUUUUUUAAAUGUGGCAUCAAUGUUUAUUUUUAAUAAUAGUAUUACUGACUUAAUAAACCCCAAAUGUCUCUUUAAGCUGAUUUAAUGGUUAUAUUAUAGAAUUUUUUAUUUCAUUGUGUGCUUAUGAGAAAAAACAUAUUUUAGAGUUGGGUUUUAAAUGGUAGACACAGAAAGUAACUUUAAAAUAUCCUAAACAAAAUAUCUAUUUCAUUUUUCUUCUUAAGUAAAAUAACAACACCUCAUUAGUGUGUAGAAGCUAUUCUAAUCCAUUAAAAUUUUAUUUUUAUAUUUAUUUAAAUAUCUACUGUACAUGACAAAAUAUAUUUCUGUGGCUGCCUUUUAUAAUUAUUUUCCAAGUAGACAUAAUCUAUUUAAAACAUAUUUUUCUAGUGACAAAGAAAUACAUUUUAUCCUGAUAUAUAGUUUUUAAAUACUAGGCUAUUUCUUUUCAUACUGCCUGAUUGGUUUAAUAAACAUGAUGUGACAAAUAUUAAGUAUAUAUCAUUUUAUCAUGUUGUAACUGAUCCAAAAUAAUAAAAGAAAUAAUUAUACCUUU